AUUCCUCGCCUGCGGUUUGGCGGGACAGCGCUGCAGCCCAUGGUGUGGAGCGCGGCUGGGGGACCAGGGGGAGGUGGGGAGAGGGGAGCGUGGAGGGGAGCGUGGAGGGGGGCGCGCGAAGGGGUUGCGGGGCGCAGGAGGCGGGCUGGGCUCGGCUGGAGACCGGACCUCGGUGUUGGCCUACAGCACAGGGAGCCGGCCGAAUGCGCGUGAUUACUGGACGGCGCUGCUCUGGGAGAGAGUCGGGGCCAGAUUUGGCGCGGCGGUGAGGCGGCUGCGGGACAAGCAGAGGCGCGCGGGCGUGGGCAAGGGUUUGGGGCGCUCUGGAGCGGUUUGUUGGGUCAGUGAGGUGCCAGGGAGAGCGGGUGCCUGCCGGGCAGUGUGCUCGGGUUGCACGCCCUAGCGCGGGGGCGACAGCGGCGGCGCGGGCGGGCGGUCUGGAAUAAUGACAAACACAUUUGGCCCUGAGUGAAGAAGUCGUCGUCGCCUCGCAUUCCAGCAACUGGGAUUUGAGGAAUUUCGAACCGCACACCAAGGGGCCCUCAUUGUGCUCCGUGGCCCCCGCCCCCGCCUGUCUUCCCGCGCCCCCUCCUCGGUGGAAUCAUUUCUGCAUUGCCCGGGGGCUCUGCUUUCGCUCAGUUCUGGCCGCAGGCAGGAAGAGAGGAAAGGUCUCCAGGAAGGUGCCGAACUUCUUGUGAGGAAGUUAGGGACGACUUGGAACUGGGGAAACUUGUUUGCAGUUUCCCAGAGCUAUGGGGACUUCCCAUCCGGCGUUCCUGGUCUUAGGCUGUCUUCUCACAGGGCUGAGCCUAAUCCUCUGCCAGCUUUCAUUACCCUCUAUCCUUCCAAAUGAAAAUGAAAAGGUUGUGCAGCUGAAUUCAUCCUUUUCUCUGAGAUGCUUUGGGGAGAGUGAAGUGAGCUGGCAGUACCCCAUGUCUGAAGAAGAGAGCUCCGAUGUGGAAAUCAGAAAUGAAGAAAACAACAGCGGCCUUUUUGUGACGGUCUUGGAAGUGAGCAGUGCCUCGGCGGCCCACACAGGGUUGUACACUUGCUAUUACAACCACACUCAGACAGAAGAGAAUGAGCUUGAAGGCAGGCACAUUUACAUCUAUGUGCCAGACCCAGAUGUAGCCUUUGUACCUCUAGGAAUGACGGAUUAUUUAGUCAUCGUGGAGGAUGAUGAUUCUGCCAUUAUACCUUGUCGCACAACUGAUCCCGAGACUCCUGUAACCUUACACAACAGUGAGGGGGUGGUACCUGCCUCCUACGACAGCAGACAGGGCUUUAAUGGGACCUUCACUGUAGGGCCCUAUAUCUGUGAGGCCACCGUCAAAGGAAAGAAGUUCCAGACCAUCCCAUUUAAUGUUUAUGCUUUAAAAGCAACAUCAGAGCUGGAUCUAGAAAUGGAAGCUCUUAAAACCGUGUAUAAGUCAGGGGAAACGAUUGUGGUCACCUGUGCUGUUUUUAACAAUGAGGUGGUUGACCUUCAAUGGACUUACCCUGGAGAAGUGAAAGGCAAAGGCAUCACAAUGCUGGAAGAAAUCAAAGUCCCAUCCAUCAAAUUGGUGUACACUUUGACGGUCCCCGAGGCCACGGUGAAAGACAGUGGAGAUUACGAAUGUGCUGCCCGCCAGGCUACCAGGGAGGUCAAAGAAAUGAAGAAAGUCACUAUUUCUGUCCAUGAGAAAGGUUUCAUUGAAAUCAAACCCACCUUCAGCCAGUUGGAAGCUGUCAACCUGCAUGAAGUCAAACAUUUUGUUGUAGAGGUGCGGGCCUACCCACCUCCCAGGAUAUCCUGGCUGAAAAACAAUCUGACUCUGAUUGAAAAUCUCACUGAGAUCACCACUGAUGUGGAAAAGAUUCAGGAAAUAAGGUAUCGAAGCAAAUUAAAGCUGAUCCGUGCUAAGGAAGAAGACAGUGGCCAUUAUACUAUUGUAGCUCAAAAUGAAGAUGCUGUGAAGAGCUAUACUUUUGAACUGUUAACUCAAGUUCCUUCAUCCAUUCUGGACUUGGUCGAUGAUCACCAUGGCUCAACUGGGGGACAGACGGUGAGGUGCACAGCUGAAGGCACGCCGCUUCCUGAUAUUGAGUGGAUGAUAUGCAAAGAUAUUAAGAAAUGUAAUAAUGAAACUUCCUGGACUAUUUUGGCCAACAAUGUCUCAAACAUCAUCACGGAGAUCCACUCCCGAGACAGGAGUACCGUGGAGGGCCGUGUGACUUUCGCCAAAGUGGAGGAGACCAUCGCCGUGCGAUGCCUGGCUAAGAAUCUCCUUGGAGCUGAGAACCGAGAGCUGAAGCUGGUGGCUCCCACCCUGCGUUCUGAACUCACGGUGGCUGCUGCAGUCCUGGUGCUGUUGGUGAUUGUGAUCAUCUCACUUAUUGUCCUGGUUGUCAUUUGGAAACAGAAACCGAGGUAUGAAAUUCGCUGGAGGGUCAUUGAAUCAAUCAGCCCAGAUGGACAUGAAUAUAUUUAUGUGGACCCGAUGCAGCUGCCUUAUGACUCAAGAUGGGAGUUUCCAAGAGAUGGACUAGUGCUUGGUCGGGUCUUGGGGUCUGGAGCGUUUGGGAAGGUGGUUGAAGGAACAGCCUAUGGAUUAAGCCGGUCCCAACCUGUCAUGAAAGUUGCAGUGAAGAUGCUAAAACCCACGGCCAGAUCCAGUGAAAAACAAGCUCUCAUGUCUGAACUGAAGAUAAUGACUCACCUGGGGCCACAUUUGAACAUUGUAAACUUGCUGGGAGCCUGCACCAAGUCAGGCCCCAUUUACAUCAUCACAGAGUAUUGCUUCUAUGGAGAUUUGGUCAACUAUUUGCAUAAGAAUAGGGAUAGCUUCCUGAGCCACCACCCAGAGAAGCCAAAGAAAGAGCUGGAUAUCUUUGGAUUGAACCCUGCUGAUGAAAGCACACGGAGCUAUGUUAUUUUAUCUUUUGAAAACAAUGGUGACUACAUGGACAUGAAGCAGGCUGAUACUACACAGUAUGUCCCCAUGCUAGAAAGGAAAGAGGUUUCUAAAUAUUCCGACAUCCAGAGAUCACUCUAUGAUCGUCCAGCCUCAUAUAAGAAGAAAUCUAUGUUAGACUCAGAAGUCAAAAACCUCCUUUCAGAUGAUAACUCAGAAGGCCUUACUUUAUUGGAUUUGUUGAGCUUCACCUAUCAAGUUGCCCGAGGAAUGGAGUUUUUGGCUUCAAAAAAUUGUGUCCACCGUGAUCUGGCUGCUCGCAACGUCCUCCUGGCACAAGGAAAAAUUGUGAAGAUCUGUGACUUUGGCCUGGCCAGAGACAUCAUGCAUGAUUCGAACUAUGUGUCGAAAGGCAGUACCUUUCUGCCCGUGAAGUGGAUGGCUCCUGAGAGCAUCUUUGACAACCUCUACACCACACUGAGUGAUGUCUGGUCUUAUGGCAUUCUGCUCUGGGAGAUCUUUUCCCUUGGUGGCACCCCUUACCCCGGCAUGAUGGUGGAUUCUACUUUCUACAAUAAGAUCAAGAGUGGGUACCGGAUGGCCAAGCCUGACCACGCUACCAGUGAAGUCUACGAGAUCAUGGUGAAAUGCUGGAACAGUGAGCCGGAGAAGAGACCCUCCUUUUACCACCUGAGUGAGAUUGUGGAGAAUCUGCUGCCUGGACAAUAUAAAAAGAGUUAUGAAAAAAUUCACCUGGACUUCCUGAAGAGUGACCAUCCUGCUGUGGCACGCAUGCGUGUGGACUCAGACAAUGCAUACAUUGGUGUCACCUACAAAAACGAGGAAGACAAGCUGAAGGACUGGGAGGGUGGUCUGGAUGAGCAGAGACUGAGCGCUGACAGUGGCUACAUCAUUCCUCUGCCUGACAUUGACCCUGUCCCUGAGGAGGAGGACCUGGGCAAGAGGAACAGACACAGCUCGCAGACCUCUGAAGAGAGUGCCAUUGAGACGGGUUCCAGCAGUUCCACCUUCAUCAAGAGAGAGGACGAGACCAUUGAAGACAUCGACAUGAUGGAUGACAUCGGCAUAGACUCUUCAGACCUGGUGGAAGACAGCUUCCUGUAACUGGCGGAUUCGAGGGGUUCCUUCCACUUCUGGGGCCACCUCUGGAUCCCGUUCAGAAAACCACUUUAUUGCAAUGCAGAGGUUGAGAGGAGGACUUGGUUGAUGUUUAAAGAGAAGUUCCCAGCCAAGGGCCUCGGGGAGCGUUCUAAAUAUGAAUGAAUGGGAUAUUUUGAAAUGAACUUUGUCAGUGUUGCCUCUUGCAAUGCCUCAGUAGCAUCUCAGUGGUGUGUGAAGUUUGGAGAUAGAUGGAUAAGGGAAUAAUAGGCCACAGAAGGUGAACUUUGUGCUUCAAGGACAUUGGUGAGAGUCCAACAGACACAAUUUAUACUGCGACAGAACUUCAGCAUUGUAAUUAUGUAAAUAACUCUAACCAAGGCUGUGUUUAGAUUGUAUUAACUAUCUUCUUUGGACUUCUGAAGAGACCACUCAAUCCAUCCAUGUACUUCCCUCUUGAAACCUGAUGUCAGCUGCUGUUGAACUUUUUAAAGAAGUGCAUGAAAAACCAUUUUUGAACCUUAAAAGGUACUGGUACUAUAGCAUUUUGCUAUCUUUUUUAGUGUUAAAGAGAUAAAGAAUAAUAAUUAACCAACCUUGUUUAAUAGAUUUGGGUCAUUUAGAAGCCUGACAACUCAUUUUCAUAUUGUAAUCUAUGUUUAUAAUACUACUACUGUUAUCAGUAAUGCUAAAUGUGUAAUAAUGUAACAUGAUUUCCCUCCAGAGAAAGCACAAUUUAAAACAAUCCUUACUAAGUAGGUGAUGAGUUUGACAGUUUUUGACAUUUAUAUUAAAUAACAUGUUUCUCUAUAAAGUAUGGUAAUAGCUUUAGUGAAUUAAAUUUAGUUGAGCAUAGAGAACAAAGUAAAAGUAGUGUUGUCCAGGAAGUCAGAAUUUUUAACUGUACUGAAUAGGUUCCCCAAUCCAUCGUAUUAAAAAACAAUUAACUGCCCUCUGAAAUAAUGGGAUUAGAAACAAACAAAACUCUUAAGUCCUAAAAGUUCUCAAUGUAGAGGCAUAAACCUGUGCUGAACAUAACUUCUCAUGUAUAUUACCCAAUGGAAAAUAUAAUGAUCAGCAAAAAGACUGGAUUUGCAGAAGUUUUUUUUUUUUUUUUCUUCAUGCCUGAUGAAAGCUUUGGCGACCCCAAUAUAUGUAUUUUUUGAAUCUAUGAACCUGAAAAGGGUCAGAAGGAUGCCCAGACAUCAGCCUCCUUCUUUCACCCCUUACCCCAAAGAGAAAGAGUUUGAAACUCGAGACCAUAAAGAUAUUCUUUAGUGGAGGCUGGAUGUGCAUUAGCCUGGAUCCUCAGUUCUCAAAUGUGUGUGGCAGCCAGGAUGACUAGAUCCUGGGUUUCCAUCCUUGAGAUUCUGAAGUAUGAAGUCUGAGGGAAACCAGAGUCUGUAUUUUUCUAAACUCCCUGGCUGUUCUGAUCGGCCAGUUUUCGGAAACACUGACUUAGGUUUCAGGAAGUUGCCAUGGGAAACAAAUAAUUUGAACUUUGGAACAGGGUUGGCAUUCAACCACGCAGGAAGCCUACUAUUUAAAUCCUUGGCUUCAGGUUAGUGACAUUUAAUGCCAUCUAGCUAGCAAUUGCGACCUUAAUUUAACUUUCCAGUCUUAGCUGAGGCUGAGAAAGCUAAAGUUUGGUUUUGACAGGUUUUCCAAAAGUAAAGAUGCUACUUCCCACUGUAUGGGGGAGAUUGAACUUUCCCCGUCUCCCGUCUUCUGCCUCCCACUCCAUACCCCGCCAAGGAAAGGCAUGUACAAAAAUUAUGCAAUUCAGUGUUCCAAGUCUCUGUGUAACCAGCUCAGUGUUUUGGUGGAAAAAACAUUUUAAGUUUUACUGAUAAUUUGAGGUUAGAUGGGAGGAUGAAUUGUCACAUCUAUCCACACUGUCAAACAGGUUGGUGUGGGUUCAUUGGCAUUCUUUGCAAUACUGCUUAAUUGCUGAUACCAUAUGAAUGAAACAUGGGCUGUGAUUACUGCAAUCACUGUGCUAUCGGCAGAUGAUGCUUUGGAAGAUGCAGAAGCAAUAAUAAAGUACUUGACUACCUACUGGUGUAAUCUCAAUGCAAGCCCCAACUUUCUUAUCCAACUUUUUCAUAGUAAGUGCGAAGACUGAGCCAGAUUGGCCAAUUAAAAACGAAAACCUGACUAGGUUCUGUAGAGCCAAUUAGACUUGAAAUACGUUUGUGUUUCUAGAAUCACAGCUCAAGCAUUCUGUUUAUCGCUCACUCUCCCUUGUACAGCCUUAUUUUGUUGGUGCUUUGCAUUUUGAUAUUGCUGUGAGCCUUGCAUGACAUCAUGAGGCCGGAUGAAACUUCUCAGUCCAGCAGUUUCCAGUCCUAACAAAUGCUCCCACCUGAAUUUGUAUAUGACUGCAUUUGUGUGUGUGUGUGUGUUUUCAGCAAAUUCCAGAUUUGUUUCCUUUUGGCCUCCUGCAAAGUCUCCAGAAGAAAAUUUGCCAAUCUUUCCUACUUUCUAUUUUUAUGAUGACAAUCAAAGCCGGCCUGAGAAACACUAUUUGUGACUUUUUAAACGAUUAGUGAUGUCCUUAAAAUGUGGUCUGCCAAUCUGUACAAAAUGGUCCUAUUUUUGUGAAGAGGGACAUAAGAUAAAAUGAUGUUAUACAUCAAUAUGUAUAUAUGUAUUUCUAUAUAGACUUGGAGAAUACUGCCAAAACAUUUAUGACAAGCUGUAUCACUGCCUUCGUUUAUAUUUUUUUAACUGUGAUAAUCCCCACAGGCACAUUAACUGUUGCACUUUUGAAUGUCCAAAAUUUAUAUUUUAGAAAUAAUAAAAAGAAAGAUACUUACAUGUUCCCAAAACAAUGGUGUGGUGAAUGUGUGAGAAAAACUAACUUGAUAGGGUCUACCAAUACAAAAUGUAUUACGAAUGCCCCUGUUCAUGUUUUUGUUUUAAAACGUGUAAAUGAAGAUCUUUAUAUUUCAAUAAAUGAUAUAUAAUUUAAAGUUA